CGGCCUCAGGUCCCGGCCCUGCCUUCUACACUGCCCCACCGCCCUGCACCCUCCACCCGGCCAGGCCCCUGCCCACGCUGUCUACCGUCCCGCAUGGGGCCCUGCAGCGGCUCCCGCCUGGGGCCCCCAGAGGCAGAGUCGCCCUCCCAGCCCCCUAAGAGGAGGAAGAAGAGGUACCUGCGACAUGACAAGCCCCCCUACACCUACUUGGCCAUGAUCGCCUUGGUGAUUCAGGCCGCUCCCUCCCGCAGACUGAAGCUGGCCCAGAUCAUCCGUCAGGUCCAGGCCGUGUUCCCCUUCUUCAGGGAAGACUACGAGGGCUGGAAAGACUCCAUUCGCCACAACCUUUCCUCCAACCGAUGCUUCCGCAAGGUGCCCAAGGACCCUGCAAAGCCCCAGGCCAAGGGCAACUUCUGGGCGGUCGACGUGAGCCUGAUCCCAGCUGAGGCGCUCCGGCUGCAGAACACCGCCCUGUGCCGGCGCUGGCAGAACGGAGGUGCGCGUGGAGCCUUCGCCAAGGACCUGGGCCCCUACGUGCUGCACGGCCGGCCAUACCGGCCGCCCAGUCCCCCGCCACCACCCAGUGAGGGCUUCAGCAUCAAGUCCCUGCUAGGAGGGUCCGGGGAGGGGGCACCCUGGCCGGGGCUAGCUCCACAGAGCAGCCCAGUUCCUGCAGGCACAGGGAACAGUGGGGAGGAGGCGGUGCCCACCCCACCCCUUCCCUCUUCUGAGAGGCCUCUGUGGCCCCUCUGCCCCCUUCCUGGCCCCACGAGAGUGGAGGGGGAGACUGUGCAGGGGGGAGCCAUCGGGCCCUCAACCCUCUCCCCAGAGCCUAGGGCCUGGCCUCUCCACUUACUGCAGGGCACCGCAGUUCCUGGGGGACGGUCCAGCGGGGGACACAGGGCCUCCCUCUGGGGGCAGCUGCCCACCUCCUACUUGCCUAUCUACACUCCCAAUGUGGUAAUGCCCUUGGCACCACCACCCACCUCCUGUCCCCAGUGUCCGUCAACCAGCCCUGCCUACUGGGGGGUGGCCCCUGAAACCCGAGGGCCCCCAGGGCUGCUCUGCGAUCUAGACGCCCUCUUCCAAGGGGUGCCACCCAACAAAAGCAUCUACGACGUUUGGGUCAGCCACCCUCGGGACCUGGCGGCCCCUGGCCCAGGCUGGCUGCUCUCCUGGUGCAGCCUGUGAGGCUCUUAAGACAGGGGCCACUCCUCCCUCCCGCUCCCACCCCCACCUUGUUGACAGGGAGCCAAGGCGAGGCGGCUGUCUGCGACCACAGCAGCCUCGAAACACCAGGCAGCAGCCUUGCUGGGAGUCCACGGUGUUUAUUGGGCCACCCCACGCAUGGCCGUGGCCCAGCUGGGCACAACCCUCACCCUGGUCUGUCAUGCCUGUUUUUCCUACACUCAGCGGCAAAGCUGCAGGAGCAGGGCUGAGCCUGGAAUAGCCCUUCCUAGUCCCCUCUUCUCAGCCCACUACCCAUCCAUCAGUCACCAGCCGUCACCUCCCCUCCCGUGCUCCAGGCUGGGGGAGGGAGAGCCCAGUGGUGGAUCCAGCCUGAAGUCCUGCCCUCUCUCAUCUGUCUGGAAAGGAGGUAGCACCUUUUUCGGGAAACGGGUUAGGGAGUAAAGACUGCACCCUACAUGGUCCUGGUGGUGGGGGGGAUAACAGUAAAGGAAUUUGCAACGUUUUAAUGCCAUGCCUGAUUUUUGGGUCAGGAGUGGUGACUUGGGUAACCACUUGGCGGGGGGGCCUGGGAUUCCCUGCUGUGUGCCGUGAUAACAGCAAAUGGUGAUAAGGAGAAAGCCAAGACCUGUGGCCUGAUGCAGGGCUGGGGGCGGGGGGUGAUCACUUCAGCAGGCACAACACACUUCACUGGCUGCGGAGGUGGAGGGGUGACUCUGGGAGCUCAGGGGCAAUGGAUCCAAAGAGGCUAGGGAGCUUGUGCCCUGGGAGACGGGGUACAGGGACUUUACUACCGCCUCUGCCAGCAGAGACCUGGCCUGAGACCCCA